GUAGGUGAGAGGCGGCUGAAGAGUUGCUGUAUUCUGGGAAUGGGCAGGGUCACUCGUCCGAACAGAGUCCUAUCCUACGCGGCGGAAGAGUGUGCCCUUUGACUUGCAUCGUCUACCUACCUCUGCCAUCCUCUACCAGCCGCAACUGCGAGGGCUGGAGCCAACUUCAGGACUGAUUGAUCAUGACUUCUAUAAAGGAGCAGGCAGCAAUUAGCAGGCUCUUAAGUUUUUUACAGGAGUGGGACAACGCUGGCAAAGUCGCAAGGAGUCACAUCCUCGACAAGUUCAUUGAAACCAACCAAGGCAAGACUGCCCCUGAACUGGAGCAGGAGUUUUCCCAGGGAGCCAGUUUGUUCCUGGUACGCUUGACCACCUCGCUUAGAAUCACCUAUAUGACUGACUCAUGUUUAGAAAAGCUUCUCAGGUCCAUUGGCAUCUUCUUAUCAGCUGUAAGCAGUAAUCGGUACCUUAUAGAAUUUCUUGAGGUUGGAGGUGUCCUAACCCUCUUGGAAAUACUUGGGCUAGAGAAGAUCAAGGAGGAGGCCAAGAAGGAAUCUGUCAAACUACUUCAGGUUAUUGCGAACUCUGGCAGGACAUACAAGGAACUCAUUUGUGAAAGCUAUGGUGUACGAUCCAUAGCAGAAUUUUUGGCAAAGUCUAAGUCAGAAGAGACCCAGGAGGAAGUGCAGGUUCUGUUGGAUUCUUUGGUCCACGGCAAUCCCAAGUACCAAAAUCAAGUGUAUAAAGGUCUAAUAGCUUUGCUGCCCUGCGAGUCCCCAAAAGCCCAGCAGCUGUCCCUGCAGACUCUCAGGACUGCCCAGCCAAUCAUUGGGACCACACACCCCAGCAUCGUGGACUGCGUGCUGAAGGUGCUGGGCACGAUGCACCUGGAAGUCCAGUAUGAAGAUUGACACACCAGCCAAAACUCAUUCUCUUCUUCCUGCCGAAGGGCACUCUGAGCCCUGGAGUGGAGAAGUCAGCUCCCCAUCCCUCCGCCGGUGUUUUCAGCACCCAGGAGAGCUGAGCAUGCAGCCUGCAGCACACAGGAUGUGGCUGCUCCCUCUGCCUUCCCAGACCACUGCUCUUUUGGAAAUCAUCAAUGAUAGUUUUCUGACAAAGUUAGAAAUCGCCAGCAUGUGUUCCUUUUUAGGCAGCAUAUGUCUGUUUGGAGUUAAACAAGUAAAGUUUGCAGGAGCUGAAGCAGAGACCUGUUCUGUGUGCUCUGUAAAUCCACGCAGUCCACAUCUCUGACCAUCUCACCAGGUGCCCUGUGUCUCCCACUGUGAGAAGGACCACACUCUUCCCCUUUCUGUUGUGCCUGGGUUGUAUGAUAUGAGCAUCCAUAGAGUGGUGCCCAGUUCUGGGGUGGCCAAGAAGUAUAAGGUCCUGGCUUCAAAGCACUCUCAAAGUUGGCCAUGGGGCCAGGUGCAGUGGCUCACGCCUGUAAUCCCAACACUUUGGGAGGCCAAGGUGGGUGGAUCACCUGAGGACAGGAGUUAGAGACCAGCCUGGCCAACAUGGUGAAACCCCGUCUCUACUAAAAAUACAAAAAAAUUAGGCAGGUGUGGUGGCGGGCGCCUAUAAUCCUAGCUACUUGGGAGGCUGAGGCAGGAGAAUUGCUUGAAUCCAUGAGGCAGAGGUUGCAGUGAGCCAAGAUCGUGCCAUUGCACUCCAGCCUGGGCAACAAGAGCAAAACUCUGUCUCAAAAAAAAAAAAAAAAAAAAAAAGUUGGCCAUGGGGUAUACGGGGAGACAGCUGCCACAGUUCUGGCUCUCCAGCCUGUCCAAGAUUCAAGCUAGGAAAGUUCUGUAGCUGUGUGAAUGAGGACCACAGUGGCCACUGCAGAGCCUCCUCUGGGGUCAUCCACCACCAGGCUGGUGGUUUCUAAGCGUGGUCCUAGGCUGCCAUGACCCAAGCCUCGCCUGUUGGAAUGCAGAAUCCAAUGAGGUCUUUUCAACAAGAUGUAUGGAGCAUGCAUUGUGUACAUGGAAUGGUUUCAGGCUCUAGGUAAACAGAAGUGAGAUGUGUCAGAUAUGUUCAUUGGAGUUCACACACUAGUGAGGAGACCAUUUAGUGGAUAGUACUAGAAUUCUAUAGCAAGAAUUCUAUACGGUGCUACGGGUUCAGAGACAUAGGACAUCUACUCCUGAGUGAAGAGUGAAGGCAGAGGAGAGCAGGCCAGGGGCAGCUUCCUGAAAGUUGAUUUCUCAGCUGAGCCUAGAAGAAUGAGUAGCAAUAGCCAGAUAAAGAAGACUUCUCAGGCCGGGCGUGGUGGCUCACACCUGUAAUCCCAGCACUUUCGGAG